GCUUCCUCCCCGCAACCCGGUGAAAGCCAACGCAAUGUUCGGUGCGGGGGACGAGGACGACACCGAUUUCCUCUCGCCGAGCGGCGGUGCCAGAUUGGCCUCACUUUUUGGACUGGAUCAGGCAGCUGCUGGCCAUGGAAAUGAAUUUUUCCAGUACACAGCCCCAAAACAGCCUAAGAAAGGCCAGGGAACGGCAGCAACAGGAAAUCAGGCAACACCAAAAACAGCACCAGCCACCAUGAGCACUCCCACAAUACUGGUCGCAACAGCAGUCCAUGCAUAUCGAUACACAAAUGGUCAAUAUGUAAAGCAGGGCAAAUUUGGUGCUGCAGUUCUGGGGAACCACACAGCCAGAGAGUAUAGGAUUCUUCUUUAUAUCAGUCAACAACAGCCAGUUACGGUUGCUAGGAUUCAUGUGAACUUUGAGCUAAUGGUUCGGCCCAAUAACUAUAGCACCUUUUAUGAUGACCAGAGACAGAACUGGUCCAUCAUGUUUGAGUCGGAAAAGGCUGCUGUGGAGUUCAAUAAGCAGGUGUGCAUUGCUAAGUGCAACAGUACCUCUUCCCUGGAUGCAGUGCUCUCCCAGGACCUCAUUGUGGCAGACGGCCCUGCUGUAGAAGUUGGAGAUUCUUUGGAAGUGGCCUAUACCGGCUGGCUCUUUCAGAAUCAUGUGCUGGGCCAGGUUUUCGACUCCACUGCUAACAAAGAUAAGUUGCUUCGCUUGAAGUUAGGAUCAGGAAAAGUCAUCAAGGGCUGGGAGGAUGGAAUGCUGGGCAUGAAAAAAGGAGGAAAGCGAUUGCUUAUUGUCCCUCCAGCCUGUGCUGUUGGCUCAGAAGGGGUAAUAGGCUGGACUCAAGCAACGGACUCGAUCCUGGUGUUCGAGGUGGAGGUUAGGCGGGUGAAGUUUGCCAGAGAUUCUGGCUCUGAUGGUCACAGUGUUAGUUCCCGCGAUUCUGCAGCUCCGUCUCCCAUCCCUGGUGCUGACAACCUCUCUGCUGAUCCUGUUGUGUCACCACCCACAUCAAUACCUUUCAAAUCAGGGGAGCCAGCUCUUCGUACCAAAUCUAACUCCCUCAGUGAACAACUUGCAAUAAAUACAAGUCCCGAUGCAGUCAAAGCCAAGUUGAUCUCUCGGAUGGCUAAAAUGGGCCAGCCCAUGCUGCCCAUCCUUCCACCACAGCUGGAUUCCAAUGAUUCAGAAAUCGAAGAUGUGAACACUCUGCAAGGAGGUGGGCAGCCUGUGGUGACUCCGUCCGUCCAGCCCUCUCUUCAUCCGGCCCAUCCAGCGUUACCACAGAUGACCUCACAGGCACCUCAGCCAUCUGUUACUGGGCUCCAGGCACCUUCUGCUGCCUUAAUGCAAGUGUCAUCUCUCGAUUCCCACUCAGCUGUAUCUGGAAAUGCCCAAUCCUUUCAGCCCUAUGCAGGUAUGCAAGCCUACGCUUAUCCCCAGGCAUCUGCCGUCACCUCCCAGCUGCAGCCCGUUCGGCCUUUGUACCCAGCACCGCUCUCUCAGCCUCCCCAUUUCCAAGGAUCAGGUGAUAUGGCUUCAUUUCUCAUGACUGAAGCCCGGCAACAUAACACUGAAAUUCGAAUGGCAGUCAGCAAAGUGGCUGAUAAAAUGGAUCAUCUCAUGACUAAGGUUGAAGAGUUACAGAAACAUAGUGCUGGCAAUUCCAUGCUUAUUCCUAGCAUGUCAGUUACAAUGGAAACAAGCAUGAUUAUGAGCAACAUCCAGCGAAUCAUUCAGGAAAAUGAAAGAUUGAAGCAAGAGAUCCUUGAAAAGAGCAAUCGGAUAGAAGAACAGAAUGACAAGAUUAGUGAACUAAUUGAACGAAAUCAGAGGUAUGUUGAGCAGAGUAACCUGAUGAUGGAGAAGAGGAACAACUCACUUCAGACAGCCACAGAAAACACACAGGCAAGAGUAUUGCAUGCUGAACAAGAGAAGGCCAAGGUGACAGAGGAGUUAGCAGCGGCCACUGCACAGGUCUCUCAUCUGCAGCUGAAAAUGACUGCUCACCAAAAAAAGGAAACAGAGCUGCAGAUGCAGCUGACAGAAAGCCUGAAGGAGACAGAUCUUCUCAGGGGCCAGCUCACCAAAGUGCAGGCAAAGCUCUCAGAGCUCCAAGAAACCUCUGAGCAAGCACAGUCCAAAUUCAAAAGUGAAAAGCAGAACCGGAAACAACUGGAACUCAAGGUGACAUCCCUGGAGGAGGAACUGACUGACCUUCGAGUUGAGAAGGAGUCCUUGGAAAAGAACCUCUCAGAAAGGAAAAAGAAGUCAGCUCAAGAGCGUUCUCAGGCCGAGGAGGAGAUAGAUGAAAUUCGCAAGUCAUACCAGGAGGAAUUGGACAAACUUCGACAGCUCUUGAAAAAGACUCGAGUGUCCACAGACCAAGCAGCUGCAGAGCAGCUGUCUUUAGUACAGGCUGAGCUACAGACCCAGUGGGAAGCAAAAUGUGAACAUUUGUUGGCCUCCGCCAAGGAUGAGCACCUGCAGCAGUACCAGGAGGUGUGCGCACAGAGAGAUGCCUACCAGCAGAAGCUGGUACAACUUCAGGAAAAGUGUUUAGCCCUCCAGGCCCAAAUCACAGCUCUCACCAAGCAAAAUGAACAGCACAUCAAGGAACUAGAGAAGAACAAGUCCCAGAUGUCUGGGGUUGAAGCUGCUGCAUCUGACCCCUCAGAGAAGGUCAAGAAGAUCAUGAACCAGGUGUUCCAGUCCUUACGGAGAGAGUUUGAGCUGGAGGAAUCUUACAAUGGCAGGACCAUUCUGGGAACCAUCAUGAAUACGAUCAAGAUGGUGACUCUUCAGCUGUUAAACCAACAGGAGCAAGAGAAGGAAGAGAGCAGCAGUGAAGAAGAAGAAGAAAAAGCAGAAGAGCGGCCACGAAGACCUUCCCAGGAGCAGUCAGCCUCAGCCAGUUCUGGGCAGCCUCAAGCACCCCUGAAUAGGGAGAGGCCAGAGUCCCCCAUGGUGCCCUCAGAGCAGGUGGUCGAGGAAGCUGUCCCGUUGCCUCCUCAGGCCCUCACCACUUCCCAGGAUGGACACAGAAGGAAAGGGGACUCAGAAGCUGAGGCACUCUCAGAGAUAAAAGAUGGUUCCCUUCCACCCGAACUGUCUUGCAUCCCAUCCCACAGAGUUCUAGGGCCCCCGACUUCAAUUCCACCUGAGCCCCUAGGCCCUGUAUCCAUGGACUCUGAGUGUGAGGAGUCACUUGCUGCCAGCCCAAUGGCAGCUAAGCCCGACAACCCAUCAGGAAAGGUCUGUGUCAGGGAAGUAGCACCAGAUGGCCCACUACAAGAAAGCUCCACAAGACUGUCCCUGACUUCAGACCCCGAGGAGGGGGACCCACUGGCCUUAGGGCCUGAAAGCCCAGGAGAGCCUCAGCCUCCACAGCUCAAGAAAGAUGAUGUCACUAGCUCCACCGGUCCCCACAAGGAGCUGUCAAGCACAGAGGCAGGUUCCACAGUUGCAGGAGCAGCCCUCAGACCCAGCCAUCAUUCCCAGCGUUCCAGUCUCUCUGGGGAUGAAGAGGAUGAACUGUUUAAAGGGGCAACUCUGAAAGCUCUGAGGCCCAAAGCACAGCCUGAGGAGGAGGAUGAAGACGAGGUGAGCAUGAAGGGACGCCCGCCCCCAACGCCCCUUUUUGGAGAUGAUGAUGAUGACGAUGACAUUGACUGGCUGGGAUGAAGACCCAGGAAACUGGUGCAAAGGUUUCUCUGCAACCCUUCCCUAAGCAUGAUUUUGCACAGCCAACCCUGGGUCUAGGCGAACCACAGGGUGAGGUCAAGGUGAGCAUUCUGGGAACAAUAUUUGGGCUCAGAGGGUGGGUUGGCCACCUUCUGAGCCCCACCCCCGCCAGACCUGGUGAAGAGGAUCAUAACCCUGUCUUCAAGAACACUGGGAUUUCAGCAGCAAGUUGGAAGAAGGACUGGUAGGUUCCCCUCCAAGCCAGUCACCUGUAAGAGUCCUGUCCUCUGCCAGACUUUUUAAUCUCUUCAUUAACUCUCAGACUGACCUGGGAGCCCUCCUCUACCUGAAUCCAGUGCUCAACUGUGCCCCGGCAACAAGACCUGGGCUGAGGUCUCCCUGGUAGAACUAAGGGAGAUUACACCAUCUAAAUCCCAGUGCAGUCAACAGCCUGGCCUAUAGUCCUGGGACAUGUAUCUUCUUCUUUGCCUUAAAUCUGAUACAAGAGGUCAAUGACUUUGAAAAUAAAACUAAAAUAAAUGUCUAUAAUGAAACUUGACCCAAGCCCUUGGAGAAAAAUUGAGUUUGGUUCCAAGGGCUGUCUGUGCUCUUUUGGGAAUCUAAGGGUAGGAGUCUUACAGAUCUGGGUCAGUUAAUGUGCACAAAACGUUGUGGCAUAUUUACUCCCUUUGAUACCUAACCCUGGAACUUUUAGGCUUUCAAAGAAAGUCACCACUGUAGUCCUAGCUCAUCCCUGGGGCAUGAUGGUUCUGUGAGGACCAGUCCAGUCAUCCUCUUGCUCCUGCAGGCUUAGUCCUGCAGUCUAGGAAGCCAUGCAAAGAAGGUGAGAGGGUCCCUUCUUUCCAUUGUUCAUGGCACCUGAGGGAUUCUUCACUUUGAGAGCAGCUUCCAUUCCCUUAGAACUCAUGGGACCAGGACUUAUGCAGAGAACAGUAGUGAGAAAAUACUUGUGGUCAUUUUCUUGAUUCCAGGAUCUUCCAAAGAUUAUGCAAUCAGUCUUUAAAAAAACAGAAUAAUUAAUUUUAAUAAAAAAUGUUUCUUGAUUUUAAAUGUUUUAAAAGAUAGGACCCAAAAUUCCACUUCAUCUGGCCUGGCAUCAUCCUUGCAGGCUUUGGAUAUGUCUCCCGUGUGCGGACCUGGGAGGCAGUGAGAACUAAUUAUUUCUUUGUUGCUUAACAAAAGGCGGUGCUGUUUGGCACUUUCACAGACUGGCUUAUCUCCAGCAACCACUGCAGAAGACAGUGUUAUCACCAUUUUAUAGAGGAGAAAACUGAGACUUAGAGAGGUAAAGUAAUUUGCCCAAAGUUACAUAUCUAGGAAGCCUCAGCACAAGAAUUCAAAUCCUGGCCAUCUGAUUCCAGAGCCUGGGCUCUUGGCCAGCACAGCCUGACUGUCACUGGUUGGGGGAAGGGGCGGUGAUGCUUUUAGAAACAGGCUUCUUGAGACACCAGGCAGCUUUCCAGUUCCCUGCAAACAUGGGGGAAUGCCCUGAUCAGUCCUAAAGGUGUGACAUAGUCUACUUUCUAGGGCAGUUAUUUCUUAUUGUAAAUUAACUAGUGGCUAUUAUAUUUGCUUCUGCCCGCAGGGAGAGAAGAUGCUGAGUAAUUGUGCCAACACAGGUGCUUAAAGUCCGUGUGACAGUUACUUUUCUUAUAGCAUGUACUCAAUUAAUACUUGUUACAUGAAUGAAGAAUGACUUGACUUGCCUCAGUUGGCAUUCUGGGGUGUCUACCUGGGUGCAGCAUUUCAGGGCUGGGUUUCCCUGAGCAGAGUUGUCUUUGUAGCAGAUGGAUGGACUCUGUCCUCAGACAGGCUUAUAAAGAGUACUACCAGUUCUAUUAGCCCCACUCAGCCCCUGCAGUUGUUACAAGGGUUCAUGUGCUUUCUGUUGGAAUUAGGAGAACAGAACAGUCAUAGACUAUUUAAAAAUAUAUAUUUACUAAAAUGUAUUUGUUUGUUUUUAAUUCCCAAAGCUUACAACCAUCUUUUCAUCUAAUCUGUGAGGUAUUUAGUAUACAGCAGUGAUUUUCUCUCUUUCCUUUUUUAUAAAGUGAAGAGGUUCAACUAUCCAGAGAGUCCCAUCUAACUCAAAAAAUGUAAUGGCUUUGGUUGGAUUGCAUCUUCAGUCAGUACCUGCCCAUGGCUUAAUCAGUAUUUUAAGUGAAUGAAUCAUGUUUCCCCACUAGAUCAUUACGAGUAAGCAGUAAGUAAUAAAUAGAGAAUAUUAAGUAUUGAACAUUAUUAGAUGCAGCUUUUUGUUCUGCAUAGAAGAAAGAUGAGGAUAAAGGAGGGCAUUGAGGCCACGAAGAGCUUCCCAGACACCCACGGCCAUCAGAUCAUCUUCUUCCUGCAGGCAGUGCCUUCUGGUGGAAGGAGCUCAGUCUAUCAGAGAAUAAACCAGGAGCCUGAAAGCAGUCCUGUGUCUCUGCCUUUAAUCAGCUGUCACUUAUUCUCUCCCCAAGAAAGGGAAAUAGGUCUCAGCAGUUUCUGCCAUCCAUCAUGAAUCAAUGAAAUCAUUUCAUUAAAAAUUUUUUUGUAUGAAUGUGCAAAAUUGCCAACUAGGAGUUCAAUGGGAAAAAUAAAAAAAACUUAGUUUGUCAACAUGAUCCAUAGACGAGAUGAUCUUCAUGUGUUCCAAAGGCAGAAAGGUGAGAAAAAGGAUCUAGCUUGGUCUCUGUCCCUCAAAGACAGAAGAGGUCAGGAAGUCCAAUGGGCGAUGCUCCUGUAGAUAAGGCACAAAGCAGGAGAGCUGAGGGUGUCCAGGUUCCAUGCCCUGCAUCACCAAGAACCCUUCUCCCUGGCUUGAAAUCUUUGGAAAUUCCUGGUUUGAGUCACAGAGAAGCAUUGUCAUGGGCUCAGUAACCCUGCCACCCCUGUUAUCUCCAUUCUCCCUUUGGUCACAGCAGCUGUCUUAAGACACAAGACCAUGCCUGGGCCCUACGUAGGCUGGCUGAGAAGGAAGGUUGCUGCAAUGGCUUCCGAACUCCAGGGAGCAAGUGCUGGCUUCAGCUCAAAGUUUCCAGGGGCUGGGAAUAAGGUGGAGGAAUAGCCAUCAGAAGAAAGGGCAGUUGGAAGUAUAGUGUCUGGAAGAGGGGGCUCCAUGUCCCUCCAGCCUCAGUGCCUGCACGUUCCUCACCAGCUAAGCUGUGCUGAGAAGUGGGUAAGCUAGGUAGUAGCCCACAGCAGAGCCCAAGACCACACCAAGGAAAAUCCAGGUGUUGUAGGACAUUACGGCCAGCAUGAUGAAGUAGCCGAUGACCACCUGGAUGACAUGGAUUAGAGACUGGCCAAAGUGACACAAAUACCACCUAGAUAAAAAGGAGAAGCAAGUUAAUCCUGGUAAUGAGCUGGUAAUGAGGAAGCUGGGAGUAGAUAUCAGGGAGUAGAAAGCUGUUGAGUUACGUGACCCGAUUGAUUUAUAACUUGUAUGCUUAACCCAGGAGUGAUUUCUUUCUGCCCCUCCCACCCCCGCCCCCAGAAAAAACUCGAGAUUUAUUUUUAAAGAGACAUAUCUUCACUACAUUUGGUUUCAAGCUUCCUGGCAUCCUAGGCAAAGGGGAAAAUGAGGGUAUCUAUAAUCUGUCUUUCUGAUAAGGAAUAAGAGAAAAUCAUCAGUAAGGCAUAUUUCCCCCCUGAAUCUACUUCGGGAGGCAGUAUGACAAUGGAAAGAAAAAGCAUGGUCUUAGGUGACAUUAUCAGUUCCUAGACCUGCCACUAACUAAAAGUGGCCUAGACAAAUGUCUUAACCUCUCUGAACGUAAGAUUCCUUAUCAGUAAAACAGGAAUGAGAAUACUUCCCUUGCAGUGCAGUUGUGAAGAUCUGAGACACCCAUGUAGGGUGGCUAGUGAUGGAGCGGGCAGGCUUAUUAAGCACAGGUGAGGCUGGGGCUGGACAGAGGGCAGAACAGGGACCCUAAAUGGUUGCCUGAUUCGAGUGGGAAGGGAGGAGAGGAGAGCUUGUCAUCCUCCUCCCACCAAGUGGGAUACAUUGCUUCAGGACAGCUGCAGAUCCCCUCCUGGAUAUGGGAGCCUAGUGACCCAUGGAACUGGUGAGAUUUGGGGGAGGGUGGGUGGCCACCUCAUUUGCUAGAUAGGGGCCUGCACCUGAAGAUCACUGUUCCCUAAAGAAAGCCUUCUGAGCCUCUCAAGUGGCUGGCUGUUCACAGAGUGCUUUGGCCUGGGCAUCAGGAGACAUGAGCUCUAGUUCACUUGGCUAUGUGUAGCCACUUUGGCAAGUCCUGGUCCUUCCCUGGGCCUCGCUGUCCUCUCUGUGAAGUGGGGCUAAUGCUGUCUGGGCCAGCCUGUCUCUCAGGGUGAAUGUGAGGCUUCUGCCCCUUUCCCAUACCCACUGCCUGUACCUGUGGUGGGUUCUGCCAACAGGGAAUGAAUCUGAGCCUGCAGAGUCCCCGUCUGUCUCUGCGAUGGUCUGCUGGCUGAUGGAGGUUGGCAGGUUCACCAGUACCUGGUUGAGCAGCUUGGCUUUGCCAACCUUGAUGCCUUCAUACAGUACAGCCAGAAGCAGGAGCACCAACACCGAAAGGGCCAUGCCUGUCAAAGGAGGCAGAGUUGUGGAGACCUGGCCAGGCCAGCACUGUUUCCCUUCCAGCACCUCCACCUGUUCAUGGAAUCCACUCCAUCCACCUCUAUCCUGCACCUUCUUCCCCACCCUUGCUGAGUUCCGAACUUCUUCACUGUCUUCACCAGACUUUUCUUAGCUGGAGUGUGGCUUUGAGAUCAGGAAGAGAAGCCACCUGAAAAAUCCAGGGGCUGAGGGUGAAGAAGCCACGUACCAUUACCCCACCCACUCCCCCAGCAGGCUGCACAAAUCUGUCGUGACUUCUUGUUAAGUGAUGAGUACUGCAAGGUCCUAUUUAUAUGUAAGUAUGCAAAAAAUGUCUGGAAGGAAAGAUAAAUAGCACAAGAGUAAUAGUUAUCUCAGCAAAGUAGGAUACAGGUGGUUUUUAUGUUCUUGCCUAACUUUCUAAGGUUUCUUUUAUAUAUAUUACUUUUAUAAUAGGGGAAAAACCCAAUAAAUUAUUUUACCAAAACUA